AGAGUCGACUGAAGUUUCCGAGGAGACUUCUCAGGCUGGGCUGGACACACCUUUCCAAGGACCCCCAAACUCUGCUCCGUGCACGUCAAAUGCUCCUUUCCCUUGUGUCCAACCCCCUACCCCUCUCCCUAACACCCCUCUUCUCAACAAGACUCAGCCUCUCCCCGAGGUGGGUGAGCAUCCUUGAGGUUUCCCACCCUUAACUGCUGUGUCCCCGGAUGGAGCCAGAGAAAUGUGGUGGGGGGGCCGGGGCCAGAGUUUCAACAUUGCCCCCCAGAAGGAGGAGCCAGAGAUGGGGUCUGUCCAGGAAAAUAGGAUGCCGGAGCCCAGGAGUCGUCAGCCUAGCAGUUGCCUGGCCUCCAGAUGCCUCCCAGGGGAGCAGAUCCUAGCAUGGGCCCCAGGGGUGAGGAAGGGCCUGGAACCAGAAUUGUCUGGAACCCUGAUCUGUACCAACUUUAGGGUCACCUUCCAGCCCUGUGGAUGGCAGUGGAAUCAGGACACUCCCUUGAACAGUGAAUACGAUUUUGCCCUGGUCAACAUUGGACGAUUAGAGGCUGUGAGCGGCUUGUCCCGAGUCCAGCUCCUCCGUCCAGGGUCCCUGCAUAAAUUUAUCCCUGAGGAGAUUCUGAUUCAUGGCCGAGACUUCCGGCUGCUCAGAGUUGGUUUUGAGGCUGGAGGCCUAGAGCCUCAGGCUUUUCAGGUGACCAUGGCCAUUGUCCAAGCCAGAGCUCAGAGCAAUCAAGCCCAACAGUAUUCGGGGAUAACCCUGAGCAAGGCUGGCCAGGGUUCUGGCUCCAGAAAACCACCAAUUCCUCUCAUGGAGACAGCGGAAGACUGGGAGACUGAGCGGAAGAAGCAGGCAGCCAGAGGCUGGAGGGUCAGCACGGUCAACGAGAGGUUCGACGUAGCCACCAGCCUCCCCCGUUACUUCUGGGUCCCUAACCGAAUUCUGGACAGUGAGGUCAGGAGAGCAUUUGGCCACUUUCAUCAGGGCCGUGGACCGCGCUUGUCCUGGCAUCACCCUGGGGGCAGUGAUCUUCUCCGCUGUGGAGGCUUCUAUACAGCCAGUGACCCUAACAAGGAGGAUAUCAGAGCAGUGGAGUUGAUGCUCCAGGCUGGGCAUUCAGAUGUUGUCCUGGUAGACACUAUGGAUGAGCUGCCCAGCCUUGCAGAUGUCCAACUUGCCCACCUGAGGCUGAGGGCCCUCUGCCUGCCUGAUUCAUCUGUAGCUGAGGAUAAAUGGCUUUCAGCCCUGGAAGGAACACGAUGGCUGGACUAUGUCAGGGCUUGUCUUCGAAAGGCCAGUGACAUUUCAGUAUUAGUGACAUCCAGGGUUCGUUCUGUAAUACUUCAAGGCUCCGGUGUUUCUCCUCUUCCUUGAUUGUGUCUGGCAGCUCCUCCAGCAGUUUCCAGCUGAUUUUGAAUUCUCUGAGUUUUUCCUUCUUGCUCUUCAUGACAGUGUCAGGGUUCCUGACACCCUUACCUUCCUGAGAAAUACCCCCUGGGAGCGCGGAAAGCAGAGCGGACAGGUCAGUGACUUCUAUUUUUGACUCGUGUUUUUUUUUCCAUUGAGAUGUACUCUCUGAAGUUUGGUCUUGAUUUGUUUUAUGAGAAGUGAGGUCUGUGAGUGGGGAGGGGGAGAUUUAUUCUCAUUUUCAGGACGAGACUUUUGCCCUACAUCUUUCCUAGAAUAAGAGGUGAGAAUCUCAUGAUUUGUCUCUAGAUGUGGGAGGAUUGUGUGUAACCAUCCUUUUUCUUGCUUCCUCUGUCCAGUUAAACUCCUAUACACAAGUCUACACCCCAGGAUACUCCCAGCCUCCAGCUGGGAACUCUUUUAACCUGCAGCUGUCUGUCUGGGACUGGGAUUUACGUUAUAGCAAUGCACAGAUACUACAAUUCCAGAAUCCUGGCUAUGACCCAGAACACUGUCCAGAUUCCUGGCUCCCUAGACCACAGGUGAAGUGUCUAAACUUCCUAAAUUCCCUUGACGUUCCCACAGGCUCAUGCUACUAGACAGUGAGAAGUGAAAGACAAAAUGUCUUGAGUUCCUUAGGGAAAGCUACUCCACUACUCUUCUGCAGCUGUCACUUAUAGUCCCUGGGUGUCCCUAGGAAGACAGAAGACCUAGAAUAGCACAGAGGGCACCCUUUUUGUCCUUCCUCAAGUCUGUUUACUCAUCUUCCUGUCUCGUGCACACAUAAGGUGCCCUAAAAUCAACCUUAAUCAGUCCCGAGGCCUAGUUGAAGCCUAAUGAGGAGGGUAGAAGAGUUCUCAUGGGGAGGCUUGUAGUUCUAGUCACCAGUGCAGUGAGUGGGUGGCAGCAGGACACCCUGUCCUGAUCCAGAUUGGGGAAACUAGGGUUAUCUGGUCUCUCUGUUGCCAGUUGAUUUUCUUUUCCUUUUAGCCAAGCUUCAUGGUUCCUGGACCCCCCAGUUCUGUGUGGCUCUUCUCUAGAGGAGCAUUGACCCCCCUGAAUCAGCUCUGUCCUUGGCGGGACAGUCCUUCCCUGCUGGCAGUCUCUUCUCGUUGGCUCCCUCGACCUGCUAUCUCCUCUGAAAGCCUGGCUGACCAGGAAUGGGGUCUCCCCUCACAUUGGGGAGCUUGCCCUUUACCUCCAGGGCUGCUGCUGCCUGGGUAUCUGGGACCCCAGAUCAGGCUCUGGAGACGCUGCUACCUGAGGGGAAGGCCUGAGGUCCAGGUAAGAAGGGAAAAUAGACUGGGAGUGGGACAAGGGACUUGACUCUGCUGAACCAGAUGAACAGGAGCUGGAAAGGCAAGGAGCUGAAGCCUCUGGGAGUCUGGGAAGUGAAGUUCUACUCCUCUUGGCAUCAAACAAGGUUUGGGAGUGUAGGAGGUGCGGGAAAGUGCUUGUGGCUUAGAUUAAGUGGAAUUUAGGGCAUAGCUGAAAGGGGAAACAGAAUUAAAGACACCAGAAGUAGCAGAGAAGCAGGGGGCCAGAGCUACAACAGUAUUCUUCUCUGUUCCUCUUUGCCUCCUCCCCAGAUGGGCCUCUCAGCUCCCACAAUCUCUGGCCUCCAGGAUGAGCUAUCCCAUCUUCAGGAGUUAUUACGGAAAUGGACACCAAGAAUAUCUCCUGAGGAUCACUCCAAGAAAAGAGAUCCACAUACCAUUCUCAAUCCCACUGAAAUUGCUGGCAUUCUCAAAGGCAGGGCAGAGGGGGAUCUGGGGUAGAGGAGGGUUCUGUCUAAUCUUUUUUUUUUUUUUUUGUAUCUGCACUUGCAGCCUCAGCUUUCACACUUCAGCCCUUAAGUUCACUAAGAAGGUCUGAGUUUCUGCUGCAGAUAGUGGUGUUAACUGCUCCAACUCUUGUCUUGCUUAGUUUCUACAAAUAUUUUUGCUUCUUGUCAUUUGAAGGAUUAAGAAACAAAAACAAUCCAGAAAUUGAUCGGUUUUUUUAGGCCAAUCCCAUCCCUUCUGGAUAACCAGAUGUUAAAUCAUGAGAUCAGAGAUGCUGUUCAUCAGUCCCAACAAGAUGGCCUAGAAAUCGCAUUCUCACCUCGCCUUGCUGCUGCUUUAAUUCCAAGUUCUAUUUCUUCCCUUAUAGUUUUCUAUGGGAAUGAGGCGGAUACAGGAAACACCCUAUCUCCUCUGUAUUUUUGUAGUGGAAUUUCUAUUUAAGGGGCUCAUUAAAGCAUAGUAUUUAUACACA